AGAACCGCGCGGGCCAAUCGCGCUGCUCCCGGGUGAUGACGUAGGCUGCGCCUGUGCAUGCGCAGGGAGGGGAGACCUUGGCGGAGCGGCGGAGGCGCCCAGCGGAGGUGAAAGUAUUGGCGGAAAGGAAAAUACAGCGGAAAAAUGCAGAGCUGGAGUCGUGUGUACUGCUCCUUGGCCAAGAGAGGCCAUUUCAAUCGAAUAUCUCAUGGCCUACAGGGACUUUCUGCAGUGCCUCUGAGAACUUACGCAGAUCAGCCGAUUGAUGCUGAUGUAACAGUUAUAGGUUCUGGUCCUGGAGGAUAUGUUGCUGCUAUUAAAGCUGCCCAGUUAGGCUUCAAGGCUUUAUUGAACAACUCUCAUUAUUACCAUAUGGCCCAUGGAAAAGAUUUUGCAUCUAGAGGAAUUGAAAUGUCCGAAGUUCGCUUGAAUUUAGACAAGAUGAUGGAGCAGAAGAGUACUGCAGUAAAAGCUUUAACAGGUGGAAUUGCCCACUUAUUCAAACAGAAUAAGGUUGUUCAUGUCAAUGGAUAUGGAAAGAUAACUGGCAAAAAUCAAGUCACUGCUACGAAAGCUGAUGGCGGCACUCAGGUUAUUGAUACAAAGAACAUUCUUAUAGCCACGGGUUCAGAAGUUACUCCUUUUCCUGGAAUCACGAUAGAUGAAGAUACAAUAGUGUCAUCUACAGGUGCUUUAUCUUUAAAAAAAGUUCCAGAAAAGAUGGUUGUUAUUGGUGCAGGAGUAAUAGGUGUAGAAUUGGGUUCAGUUUGGCAAAGACUUGGUGCAGAUGUGACAGCAGUUGAAUUUUUAGGUCAUGUAGGUGGAGUUGGAAUUGAUAUGGAGAUAUCUAAAAACUUUCAACGCAUCCUUCAAAAACAGGGGUUUAAAUUUAAAUUGAAUACAAAGGUUACUGGUGCUACCAAGAAGUCAGAUGGAAAAAUUGAUGUUUCUAUUGAAGCUGCUUCUGGUGGUAAAGCUGAAGUUAUCACUUGUGAUGUACUCUUGGUUUGCAUUGGCCGACGACCCUUUACUAAGAAUUUGGGACUAGAAGAGCUGGGAAUUGAACUAGAUCCCAGAGGUAGAAUUCCAGUCAAUACCAGAUUUCAAACUAAAAUUCCAAAUAUCUAUGCCAUUGGUGAUGUAGUUGCUGGUCCAAUGCUGGCUCACAAAGCAGAGGAUGAAGGCAUUAUCUGUGUUGAAGGAAUGGCUGGUGGUGCUGUGCACAUUGACUACAAUUGUGUGCCAUCAGUGAUUUACACACACCCUGAAGUUGCUUGGGUUGGCAAAUCAGAAGAGCAGUUGAAAGAAGAGGGUAUUGAGUACAAAGUUGGGAAAUUCCCAUUUGCUGCUAACAGCAGAGCUAAGACAAAUGCUGACACAGAUGGCAUGGUGAAGAUCCUUGGGCAGAAAUCGACAGACAGAGUACUGGGAGCACAUAUUCUUGGACCAGGUGCUGGAGAAAUGGUAAAUGAAGCUGCUCUUGCUUUGGAAUAUGGAGCAUCCUGUGAAGAUAUAGCUAGAGUCUGUCAUGCACAUCCGACCUUAUCAGAAGCUUUUAGAGAAGCAAAUCUUGCUGCGUCAUUUGGCAAAUCAAUCAACUUUUGAAUUAGAAGAUUAUAUAUAUUUUUUUCUGAAAUUUCCUGGGAGCUUUUGUAGAAGUCACAUUCCUGAACAGGAUAUUCUCACAGCUCCAAGAAUUUCUAGGACUGAAUUAUGAAACUUUUGGAAGGUAUUUAAUAGGUUUGGACAAAAUGGAAUACUCUUAUAUCUAUAUUUUACAUAAAUUUAGUAUUUUGUUUCAGUGCACUAAUGUGUAAGACAAAAAGCUACUUAUUGUAGCAUCCUGGAAUAUCUCCGUCAACUCAUAUUUUCAUGCUGUUCAUGAAAGAUUCAAUGCCCCUGAAUUUAAAUAGCUUUUUUCUCUGAUACAGAAAAGUUGAAUUUUACAUGGCUGGAGCUAGAAUUUGAUAUGUGAACAGUUGUGUUUGAAGCACAGUGAUCAAGUUAUUUUUAAUUUGGUUUUCACAUUGGAAACAAGUCAGUCAUUCAGAUAUGAUUCAAAUGUCUAUAAACCGAACUGAUGUAAGUAAACGGUCUCUCACUUGUUUUAUUUAACCUCUAAAUUCUUUCAUUUUAGGGGUAGCAUUUGUGUUGAAGAGGUUUUAAAGCUUCCAUUGUUGUCUGCAACUCUGAAGGGUAAUUAUAUAGUUACCCAAAUUAAGAGAGUCUAUUUACGGAACUCAAAUACGUGGGCAUUCAAAUGUAUUACAGUGGGGAAUGAAGAUACUGAAAUAAACGUCUUAAAUAUUCAUUUACUGGUUAUCAUGAGUACGUGUUGAGAUGGUCAUAGUUUUUUUUAUGACUACUUCUAGUGUAUAUUCUAAUUUCUUUUCUAGGCCUGAAUGUAUCUUUAUUUUCAUGUUAUAGGACAAUAUUAAGGCAUUUUAAAGGUCAUCAUCCUUUCAUCUAUUUUAGAUACACCUACUAAAUGUUUAAUAUAUACUUUUGGAGAAGUACAACAUAAGGGAGUCUUUAAUCUGUGUUUUCCUUGGCUGGGUUAAUGACUGUUUAUUUAAAGAGUGUUGUAAAAUUGGAUGUGUGGUGUUUAAAAUGGCCAUGUCCUGAGGAAACUUAAGUAACAAAGUACUAAAUGCUAAGUAGGCUUUUGCAUAUUGUAACUAAAUUUAAGAAUAAUUCAGAUUAAGUAGUUCUGAAAUUUGGUAUAGAUAGCAUAGAUUGUCUCAUGCUCAUGAGUGACAUAAUGACCCUGGAUUCUGUUACAUACUUCUAAAGAAAAUUGAUUGUUGUCUUAGGAGGCAGUUAACUUGGCUGAACACCAACUCCACACUCUGUCUUGUUUGUAGGUGGCAGCAGCUGAAAUCUCUUCUCAGUUGUUUUAGCUUUAGCUAUGCUGCUGGAAGUCUUUCCCAUGCAAGUGUGUAGUUCAGGGGUCAACCAGAGUUUGGGCAGAAGGAAGUCUGCCCCUUCUGUGCCUCCUGUUUUUUGGGGGUUUCCCCUUUAUGUUCCAGCUGUUGUGGUUGCCCCAUAUUCUGCCUUCUGAUCCUUAACCAAUAAAACUUGGCUUUUGUUUCCCCCUCAAGUGAGAACCCGUUAAAAAUGAGACAUUGAGCCAGUGCUGUUCACUUUUUAAGUGCCAACUUCCCUCUACUUUCCACUUGUUUAUAGUUGUUUCCAGUGCCUUUAGUUUUUUCUAAAAUAUAUUUGUUCAGAGUUUGCAGUUGCUAUCAGCAGGAGGGUUGGUCUGAUAUCUGUGUGCUACUUUGCCAUUAUUGGAAGUGAACUCUGCAUCUUUUUAAAAAUUUGAAAUCCCGGUAUCAUGUGAAGUGCUGUUUAUGUAAAUCUCAACAUAUCCCUUACUCAGGGAAAAAAAAGUUUUUAGUUAGGGAAUAGUGAAAUAUAAUUUAAUAUGGAAUUCUAGCUGUAGAGUUAAAUCCAUCUUUAAGUGUUUACAUUCAGUAUGAGAAUGCAAAUUUAUCUGUAUGGGGAAUAAAGUCCUAGGAAUAAAACAAGUUUUAAGUGUUCA